ACUUUCUUCCCUGAAGGAGCAGCACAGAACAAAAGCUCCAGGCAGCUGCUUCCGCUGUUUCGGGGGUAGGGCGGAGUGACAGCCCCACGGGCCACGCAGCAAGCAGAAGAUCCCCGGGAGUCACCCUCAACCCUCUGGGGCCACGUGGCUUGCCACAAAACUUCCCAUCUGUGGAUCUCCAGGCCCAUGAAUACCAGCCUGUCUGCGAGUUAGACGCCAGUCCUGGUGGCCCGGGAAGCCCAGAUCCGCAUCAGCGGUUCUGCACCCCACACCAGCAUGUGCUCACUGCCUGUGCCCCGGGAGCCCCUGCGUCGCGUGGCUGUGACUGGGGGCACGCAUGGCAACGAGAUGUCGGGCGUCUACCUGGCCCGGCACUGGCUGCAUGCCCCCGCAGAGCUGCAGAGAGCCAGCUUCUCCGCUGUGCCUGUGCUGGCCAACCCGGCAGCCACAUCCGGCUGCCGCCGCUACGUGGACCAUGACCUCAACCGCACCUUCACCAGCAGCUUCCUCAAGCCAGGCUCUGGCCAGCUCAGUUCCAGGCCCACCCCGGACGACCCAUAUGAGGUGACAAGAGCCCGAGAGCUGAACCAGCUGCUGGGGCCCAAGGCCUCGGGCCAGGCCUUUGACUUUGUCCUUGACCUGCACAACACCACGGCCAACAUGGGCACCUGCUUAAUCGCGAAGUCCUCCCACGAAGUCUUUGCCAUGCACCUGUGCCGCCAUCUGCAGCUGCAGUACCCCGAGCUGUCCUGCCAGGUCUUCCUGUACCAGCGGUCUGGGGAGGAGAGCUACAACCUGGACUCUGUGGCCAAAAAUGGACUGGGUCUGGAGCUGGGCCCCCAGCCACAGGGUGUGCUGCGGGCUGACAUUUUCUCAAGGAUGAGGACCCUGGUGGCCACAGUUCUGGACUUCAUCGAACUCUUCAACCAGGGUACGGCCUUUCCUGCCUUUGAGAUGGAAGCCUAUAGACCCGUGGGCGUCGUGGACUUCCCCCGCACCGAGGCCGGGCACCUGGCAGGCACUGUGCAUCCUCAGCUGCAGGACCGAGACUUCCAGCCACUGCAGCCUGGUGCUCCCAUCUUCCAGAUGUUCAGUGGGGAGGACCUGCUCUAUGAGGGAGAGUCCACGGUGUACCCCGUGUUCAUUAACGAGGCUGCCUACUAUGAGAAGGGCGUUGCCUUUGUCCAGACUGAGAAGUUCACAUUCACCGUGCCUGCCAUGCCCGCGCUGACCCCUGCCCCGAGCCCAGCUUCCUAACCCAAGACACACCUCCCCAACCUCAGUCUUCCCAUCUGAACGAUGGGUCCUGAGGCACAGCUCUGAGCACAGAGGUCCCUUCUGCCACCUACCAUGCACCAUGUUCCUUGCCAGGCCUCCCCAACCCCUGGCCUCAAUUUCCCUUUCUAUAAAAUGGAAGAUGUCCAGA